GGAGCCGCGGGGCCAGCGAGCUGAGGAGCAGGUGCUCGGAGCCCAGCCGCGCCAGCGUCGCGCGGCCGCUGCCCAAGUUCGCCUGGGGCCCAAAGAGGGUUCUCCCGGGCAACCGGGGAAGGAGCUUAGCCGGCGUCACGGCCACCGCGAGCUCGGAGUCUCGAGAGGAGAAGGGCGCGCGGAGCAGCGAGUCCGGGUCACCCCCGGGAGGUGUUGGCGGGUCCCCGCAGUCCCCAGCUCUUGUCGCCGCGGGGGCAGAGAGAAGACGCGAGAGACAGCAAGGCUGGGCUUUUCUGGAGACGCGAGGCACCUGGGAGAGCCGAGGCGAGAAGCGACACUUCCCUGCGGCUAGCAUCCUUGAAGGACCCCGGCGGCGAACAGCCUCCCGCAGGACGCCCUGAGAAGCUCUCAGCCCCAGGCGAGAGCGGGCGCCUGGCAGGACUUAGGCGCAGGACUUGGGGAAGCCUAAGCAGGUCUCUGCCGAGCGCAGCCCAGGGAGCAGUAACAAGGAAGGGUCCUGGAGGGGAAGGGAAAGAAGGCGGCAGCCGGCAAGGCGACCACUCACCCCCGUACACACCCACCCCGCCCGCCCAGCCAGGAGCCGCGGUGCGCCUCUGGGGGCGCUCGUUCCUUGGCGCCUUCUCUCCCGUGUCCCAGCACCGCUGGGCUACGGGCCGGGCUGGUGGGGUCCCUGGGGAUGUCCAGAUCAGGCAUGGUGGCCGAGUGGCCCUUCUCCCAGGACCAGCGUAAAAGCUGGGGUUAGGCGGGGCAGGGGGGACUCGGCUCAGGGUCCCCCGAGGUCCAGGACGAGGGAAGGCGGGCGCAGCACCCAGGGACUGGAGAGGCGGCUCCCAGUGGGACCCCUCCAGAAGUAGUGCCGGGCGCCGGGCAUCCUCCAGGAAGACCAGGGGCCGGGAAAGCCUGGGAGGCGCUCGGGAGAGGCCACUGCCAGGGGCUGCGGGCUGAGGCGGCGCUCAGCCCCGGGCGGGCGCCCGCGGAGGCGGCAGCGGCGGCGCCGGGCGGGCAUGCCGCGCCACCGGAGCUCCUUUCGGGCGCACGCUUCCCUGGCGCGGGCUGCGCGCGGCUGCCGCUGCUGCUGCUUCCACUGCUGCUGCGGACUCCCAUGGCGGCUCCGCCCGGCCGGGGCCGCCGCCGCUGCCGCCAGCCGCGGGCUGAAUGAAUGAGCCGGAUUGGCGGAGCCGGGCUGCCCGCAGCCGCGCUCACCGGCCCGGGACGCUUCCGCAUGGCCCGCGAGGAGCCGGCGCCCGCGGCGUUGGCGGCUGCCGGGCAGCCCGGGGGCGGCAGAGGCGGCGAGCGGGCGCUGCAGGGGCCAGGGGUCGCCCGCAGGGGGCGGCCAUCGCUGAGCCGCGCUAAACUGCACGGGCUGCGGCACAUGUGUGCCGGGCGCACGGCGGCUGGGGGCUCCUUCCAGCGGCGGGCGCUGUGGGUGCUGGCCUUCUGUACAUCCUUCGGCUUGCUGCUGUCCUGGUCCUCGAACCGCUUGCUCUACUGGCUCAGCUUCCCGUCACACACGCGGGUGCACCGCGAGUGGAGCCGCCAGUUACCCUUCCCCGCCGUCACUGUGUGCAACAACAACCCGCUGCGCUUCCCGCGCCUCUCCAAGGGGGACCUCUACUAUGCCGGCCACUGGCUCGGGCUGCUGCUGCCCAACCGCACCGCGCGCCCGCUUGUCAGCGAGCUGCUGCGGGGCGACGAGCCGCGCCGCCAGUGGUUCCGCAAGCUGGCGGACUUCCGCCUCUUCCUGCCUCCGCGCCACUUCGAGGGAAUCAGCGCCGCCUUCAUGGACCGCCUGGGCCACCAGCUGGAGGACAUGCUGCUCUCCUGCAAGUACCGCGGCGAGCUCUGCGGGCCGCACAACUUCUCCUCCGUGUUUACAAAAUAUGGGAAGUGUUACAUGUUUAACUCAGGCGAGGAUGGCAAACCUCUGCUCACCACGGUCAAGGGGGGGACAGGCAACGGGCUGGAGAUCAUGCUGGACAUUCAGCAGGAUGAGUACCUGCCCAUCUGGGGAGAGACAGAGGAAACGACAUUUGAAGCAGGAGUGAAAGUUCAGAUCCACAGUCAGUCUGAGCCACCUUUCAUCCAAGAGCUGGGCUUUGGGGUGGCUCCAGGGUUCCAGACCUUUGUGGCCACACAGGAGCAGAGGCUCACAUACCUGCCCCCACCGUGGGGUGAGUGCCGAUCCUCAGAGAUGGGCCUCGACUUUUUUCCUGUUUACAGCAUCACCGCCUGUAGGAUUGACUGUGAGACCCGCUACAUUGUGGAAAACUGCAACUGCCGCAUGGUUCACAUGCCAGGGGAUGCCCCUUUUUGUACCCCUGAGCAGCACAAGGAGUGUGCAGAGCCUGCCCUAGGUCUGUUGGCGGAAAAGGACAGCAAUUACUGUCUCUGCAGGACACCCUGCAACCUAACCCGCUACAACAAAGAGCUCUCCAUGGUGAAGAUCCCCAGCAAGACAUCAGCCAAGUACCUUGAGAAGAAAUUUAACAAAUCAGAAAAAUAUAUCUCAGAGAACAUCCUUGUUCUGGAUAUAUUUUUUGAAGCUCUCAAUUAUGAGACAAUUGAACAGAAGAAGGCGUAUGAAGUUGCUGCCUUACUUGGUGAUAUUGGUGGUCAGAUGGGAUUGUUCAUUGGUGCUAGUAUCCUUACAAUACUAGAGCUCUUUGAUUAUAUUUAUGAGCUGAUCAAAGAGAAGCUAUUAGACCUGCUUGGCAAAGAGGAGGACGAAGGGAGCCACGAUGAGAAUGUGAGUACUUGUGACACAAUGCCAAACCACUCUGAAACCAUCAGUCACACUGUGAACGUGCCCCUGCAGACGACCCUGGGGACCUUGGAGGAGAUUGCCUGCUGACACCCCUCGAGUCACCCAGCACUCCCUCCAAACAGACCUUGAGGCCCAAGACCCAGGACAAGGAACAGCAAGCUCAGGUGGGAUGGCCCCAGUGCUGGAAAGAAGCAAGAGCCCCCUAUGCACACAUUGCAGACUAGCUGCCUAGACCUCGCUCCGGCCACGUCCAACACGACGCAUCCUUGGGCCCCGCCGUGCGUCCCUCUUAGGAGAGAUGAGUCACACUCUGGAACUGUCCAAGAACGAACCUGCCAUCACAUCUCACUGCCAGAUGUAUAAAGCACCUGCAUGCUCAGACUUCUUGUGGCGCCACCUCCACGUCUGUCUUGUACAUGACACUCCUCCACGCGGUUUCCAGUGUCCACACUGCUGCCCGUGCAGUGGGACCAGAUUCCAGGUCCAAAGUCACCAUGAGGCCACCCUGGAAUCAGAACUGCACAAUCAAGAGGGAACCCAUGGGACUCUCUGCUACAUUCAGUUCUUGUGUCGUUUGUGAAAGUUCUUAACCUGCCCAAAAACCCCCUUUUCCCCAAGCUGCCCAUGGGGCUUCGGCGCCAAAGGUGACCCGCGCCAACCUCCCUCCCCCCCAGUGCCUAUGACGGCGGCACAGCAGCCAGCGGGUGGGGGACGCCUGUGUUCACCCAUGGUGCCCAUGUCGUUCUUCUCUCCCUGUGACACAGCUUGUACAGUCUGAUUCUUUUUAUCUGGGGUAGGGGGGCUUUUAUGUUUGUCCGAUGGAGAUUUGUUUUGUUUUGCUUCAUUUUAUGCUUUUUUAUUUUAGUUUUGAUGUUCUGAGGUUUGCUUUGGUUUUUCCAUUUUCUUUGGCAUUUAUUUAUUCGUGCUUCAAAUCACAGUCAUAUUAAAAGCUGGUCUUGUGGAAA